CGGUCCUGUGCGCACGCAUCGCACACGCCGGCGCCUUCCUUUGGGAGCCCGGGCCGGUGGCGCGGGCGCUCGGCAAAUGGAGUGGGUGCUCGCGGAAGCGCUGCUCUCGCAGAGCCGGGACCCCCGGGCCCUGCUUGGGGCGCUGUGCCAAGGGGAGGCAUCCGCGGAGCGCGUGGAGACGCUGCGCUUCCUUCUGCAGCGGCUCGAGGACGAGGAGGCGCGCGGCAGCGGGGGCGCAGGCGCGCUCCCGGAGGCGGCGCGCGAGGUGGCUGCAGGGUACCUCGUGCCACUGCUGCGGAGCCUGCGCGGACGCCCCGCGGGCGGCCCGGACCCCAGUCUGCAGCCUCGCCACCGCCGGCGCGUGCUGAGGGCGGCGGGCGCGGCCCUGCGCUCGUGCGUCCGCCUGGCCGGGCGUCCGCAGCUGGCGGCCGCGCUGGCUGAGGAGGCGCUGCGCGAUCUGCUCGCCGGGUGGCGCGCGCCUGGCGCCGAGGCUGCCGUGGAAGUGCUAGCAGCCGUCGGGCCAUGUUUGCGGCCCCGCGAGGACGGGCCGCUACUGGAGCGCGUGGCGGGGACCGCCGUCGCCCUGGCGCUGGGCGGGGGCGGGGACGGGGAUGAGGCCGGGCCUGCCGAGGACGCGGCGGCGCUGGUGGCCGGGCGACUGCUGCCAGUGCUGGUCCAAUGUGGCGGGGCGGCGCUGCGGGCCGUGUGGGGCGGGCUGGCCGCGCCUGGGGCGUCCCUGGGGUCCGGCCGCGUAGAGGAGAAGCUGCUGGUCCUGAGCGCCCUGGCCGAGAAGCUGUUGCCCGAGCCCGGCGGCGACCGCGCCCGCGGCGCGCGCGAGGCGGGCCCGGACGCCCGGCGCUGCUGGCGCUUCUGGAGGACGGUGCAGGCGGGGCUGGGCCAGGCGGACGCCCUGACGCGCAAGCGAGCGCGCUACCUGCUGCAGAGGGCGGUGGAGGUGUCGGCGGAGCUGGGGGCCGACUGCACCUGCGGGCCCCAGGAAGGAAACGGCCCAAGUCUGUUUUGGUGGUCUGAGAGGAAAAAAGAUGAGCUUCUAAAGUUUUGGGAAAAUUAUAUUUUAAUUAUGGAGACUUUAGAAGGAAAUCAGAUACAUGUUAUAAAGCCAGUUUUACCAAAGCUAAACAAUCUGUUUGAAUAUGCGGUGUCAGAGGAAAAUGGAUGUUGGCUCUUUCACCCAUCCUGGCAUAUGUGUAUUUAUAAAAGAAUGUUUGAAAGUGAAAACAAAAUCCUGUCCAAAGAAGGUGUUAUCCAUUUUUUGGAGCUGUAUGAAACAAAGAUUCUUCCAUUUUCACCAGAAUUUUCUGAGUUUAUUAUUGGACCAUUAAUGGAUGCGCUUUCAGAGAGCUCUCUGUAUAGCAGGUCCCCAGGCCAGCCAAUAGGAAGCUGUUCUCCAUUGGGACUGAAAUUACAGAAGUUUUUAGUCACUUAUAUUUCUCUUCUUCCAGAAGAAAUAAAGAGUAGCUUCCUAUUGAAGUUUAUUCGGAAGAUGACAAGUAGGCAUUGGUGUGCUGUUCCCAUUUUGUUUCUAUCUAAGGCUUUGGCAAAUGUCCCAAGACAUAAGGCCCUGGGUAUAGAUGGGCUUCUUGCUCUCAGGGAUGUUAUUCAUUGCACUAUGAUCACACAUCAGAUUCUCCUGAGAGGGGCAGCCCAAUGCUACCUUCUUCAAACAGCUAUGAAUUUGCUAGAUGUGGAGAAAGUGUCACUUUCUGAUGUCUCAACUUUUCUCAUGUCUCUGAGACAAGAGGAAUCCUUAGGACGAGGAACUUCAUUGUGGACAGAGCUGUGUGACUGGCUACGUGUUAAUGAAAGCUAUUUUAAGCCAUCCCCUACGUGUAGCUCCAUUGGACUUCACAAGACAUCUUUAAAUGCUUAUGUAAAGAGCAUUGUUCAAGAGUAUGUUAAGUCAUCUGCUUGGGAAACAGGAGAAAACUGCUUUAUGCCUGAUUGGUUUGAAGCCAAGCUUGUUUCUCUGAUGGUCUUGCUGGCUGUGGAUGUGGAAGGAAUGAAGACUCAGUAUAGCGGAAAGCAGAGAACAGAGAAUGUAUUGCGGAUAUUCUUAGACCCUCUUCUGGAUGUGCUUAUGAAGUUUAGUACCAAUGCCUACAUGCCCUUGCUGAAGACUGACAGAUGCCUCCAGCUGCUGUUGAAGCUGUUGAACACAUGCAGGUUGAAAGGUUCCAGUGCCCAAGAUGAUGAGGUGUCUACUGUUCUUCAGAACUUUUUCAUGUCUACUACAGAGAGCAUUUCUGAAUUUAUUCUCAGAAGACUUACUAUGAAUGAGCUAAAUAGUGUUUCAGAUCUGGAUCGUUGCCAUUUAUACCUGAUGGUGUUAACUGAGCUUAUAAAUCUGCAUUUGAAGGUUGGGUGGAAAAGGGGUAACCCUAUCUGGAGAGUUAUUUCUCUUUUGAAAAAUGCAUCCAUUCAGCAUCUUCAAGAGAUGGACAGUGGACAGGAGCCAACAGUUGGAAGUCAGAUUCAGAGAGUAGUGAGCAUGGCUGCCUUGGCCAUGGUGUGUGAGGCCAUAGACCAGAAGCCUGAGCUGCAGCUGGACUCUCUCCAUGCUGGGCCCCUGGAAAGCUUCCUUUCCUCUCUUCAGCUCAAUCAGACGCUGCAGAAGCCCCACGCAGAGGAGCAGAGCAGUUAUGCUCACCCCUUGGAGUGCAGCAGUGUUUUGGAAGAAUCGUCAUCUUCCCAAGGAUGGGGAAAAAUAGUUGCACAAUAUAUUCAUGAUCAAUGGGUGUGCCUCUCUUUCCUGUUGAAAAAAUAUCACACCCUUAUACCAACCACAGGGAGUGAAAUUCUGGAACCGUUUCUACCUGCCGUUCAGAUGCCAAUAAGGACUUUGCAGUCUGCACUAGAAGCCCUCACAGUUCUUUCUUCUGAUCAAGUUUUACCAGUGUUCCAUUGCUUGAAAGUGUUGGUUCCCAAGCUUCUGACUUCCUCUGAAUCACUCUGCAUAGAGUCUUUUGACAUGGCGUGGAAAAUUAUAUCUUCUUUAAGCAACACUCAGCUGAUAUUCUGGGCUAAUUUAAAAGCUUUUGUUCAGUUUGUUUUUGAUAACAAAGUUCUUACCAUUGCUGCCAAAAUCAAGGGCCAGGCAUAUUUCAAAAUAAAAGAGAUUAUGUACAAGAUAAUUGAAAUGUCUGCUAUAAAGACUGGAGUCUUCAAUACACUGAUAAGUUACUGCUGUCAGUCUUGGAUAGUGUCUGCUUCAAAUGUGUCCCAAGGAUCUUUAUCAAGUGCUAAAAAUUAUAGCGAACUUAUCCUUGAGGCUUGUAUAUUUGGAACUGUGUUUAGGCGUGAUCAAAGACUUGUUCAGGAUGUACAGACCUUCAUAGAAAACCUUGGACAUGACUGUGCGGCAAAUAUUGUUAUGGAAAAUACUAAGAGAGAAGACCAUUAUGUGAGAAUUUGUGCUGUCAAAUUCCUGUGUUUAUUAGAUGGCUCCAAUAUGUCCCACAAGUUGUUUAUUGAGGAUCUUGCAAUCAAGCUAUUAGAUAAAGAUGAAUUAGUGUCCAAGUCCAAAAAACGCUACUAUGUGAAUUCUCUACAGCACAGAGUGAAAAACCGAGUGUGGCAGACUCUGCUGGUACUUUUCCCUAGACUUGACCAGAAUUUCUUGAAUGGAAUUAUUGACAGGAUUUUCCAGGCUGGUUUCACCAACAAUCAAGCAUCCAUAAAAUAUUUUAUAGAAUGGAUUAUUAUAUUGAUUCUUCAUAAAUUCCCUCAAUUUCUUCCAAAGUUCUGGGAUUGUUUUUCUUAUGGUGAAGAAAAUCUUAAAACAAGCAUUUGUACGUUUUUAGCAGUUUUAUCACAUUUAGACAUUAUUACUCAAAAUAUUCCAGAAAAGUGUGUAUCAGCCAGAUGGCAGUGUGUUACAGUUCCAGGAAAACUCGUUCACAUCUUCCGUAAGAUCAAGAAGGCUCUGGCAUCAGAUAAGAUCAAAUGUUGUCUUUCUGUUUUAAAUAUGUGCCGCAAAGAGAUUUGCUUACAAUCUAUUGAGAAAGCUAAAACAGAGCAGACAUUGUCCUGUUGCGGGGUAGAUGAAUAGCCUAAGAAUAGUUUAGACAAAUUCUGAAAACGAAUUUACCUUAGAAGAUGUUCAUGUUAGAUCUGGUAAAAGUAACAUGUUAUUUUUCUGUCAAGCCCUUUUUGUACUUGCCGUUUAUUACAUAUUUUAGAUUUAUUUUUUAUUUUCGAAACAUCCAAAAAGGAAUGCUAAUUAGUGAAAUGGAAGAAUUUCCAUUUCAACACCUUAGGAAAAAAAAAACUGACUUGACAUACCUAAGAAAAGGCCAAGUUGAUUUACUUUGUCAGUCUCUUCAUUUGUGAUACGUAAAGUCCGUUGUUACCUAGAUAAAUGUAGGUUUGAUUUCUUGGAAGCAAUCACUUAAGACUUUCCAUUUUCUUCAAAGCAUCUUACUUAACCUGCAUGUGGGAUCUGUACUGAGCAAUUAGAGAUUCAAAACAACUGUCACACACGACAGAGGUGGUAACCGCCCAACAGGUUCACCUCUUCCGCCGCCUACACAGAGCCGAUUUAUCAAGACAGGAAUUGCAAUAGAGGAAGAGUACACAGAGCUGCUUGUGCAGGAGACUGGAGUCUUAUUAGUACUCAAAUCGAUCUCCCUGAGCAUUCGGGGAUCAGAGUUUUUAAGGAUAAUUUGGUGGGAGGGGGAAGGCCAGUGAGUCAAGGGUGUUGAUUGGUUGGGUCGGAGAUGAAAUCAUAAGGAAUUGAGGUGUCCUUUUGUGCUAAGUCAGUUCCAGGGUGGGGGCCACGAGAUCAGAUGAGCCAGUUAAUCGAUCUGGGUGGUGCCAGCUGAUCCGUCGAGUGCAGGUCUGCAAAAUAUCUCGAGCACCGACAUAGGAGCAGUUUAGGGAGGGUCAGAAUCUUGUAGCUUCCAGCUACAUGACUCCUGAACCAUAAUUUCUAAUCUUGAGGCUAAUUUGUUAGUCCUACAAAGGAAAUCUAGUCCCCAGACAAGAAGGGGGUUUGUCUUGGGAAAGGGCUGUUAUCAUCUUUGUUUUAAACUAUAAACUAAACUAAGUUUCUCCCAAAGUUAGUUGAGCCUACACCCAGGAAUGAACAAGGACAGCUUGGAGGUUAGAAGCAAGAUGGAGUUGGUUAGGUCAGAUCUCUUUCCCCACCUCAGUUACAAUUUUGCAAAGGCGGUUUCAGAAUCAGAGCACGAAGUGUUCCUAUAAAAGGAAAAAAAAAAAAAACCUUUCUUAAUUAUGCUCAUAGUUGUGUAUUGUCCUGUCAGCUUGCUCAUUGUGUAAAAUGAGCGGACAUGAGAAUUCACGAGCAGAGCUUUUUACACUGAUAUGUAUGAAAGCAUCAUUUACGUCCUGAAAGCCCCAGCCGAGCGAUCACUGGCAGUGCCAACAUUUUUGAGUGUGGGCUCCAUAGGAAGCACUGUUUUCCCUAUUGAGAAUUAUAGUGGGUUUUUUUCAUUUACGAGUAAUGUAUACCUAGCUCCAAGAUCUUGGUUGCUAACACCAUUCUCCAAUAAAACGAACCAGGGAUCGCUGGAGAAAUAGCUGAUUCUAAAACUAGGGCAGAAAGUAUACAAGAUGAGCCUGGAGCAUCUUGUAGAGUCAGAGAGCAAGGCAGAACUUUAUACAUACAGUGAUGUGAGAUGGGCAUGCAGAGGGAAGAUGUUCCCAGUGGCUGAAGCUGAAACAGUGUGAGCAACAAAAUAAAGCAGUGUUGGAUCACAACCCAAA